ACAUUAGCUGGGCGCUGAUUAGGUUAGGAUGUUGCCCAGGUACAAGGCCAGGAUCUUCGGGGCCUGGCUUCAUUUGGAGUUCAGCUACCAAAAGGAAACCUUCCUCUGGGUCCUGGAGUAUUUGGCCUGAAAUUGGGAACUCGGAAGUUGCUGCUCCAGGGCGCUCCCUGCGGAGCUCCGCCGCCCGCCUCUCCGCCCGGCCUUUCCCGGCGUCCCCACGCGGGGCGCAACCGCGAGAAAGAAACGCAGGUCGCACCGUCAGCGCCCAGAGCAGCGCCAGUUUCCGGGCCCGGGCUGCUCUCGGAGCCAUGAGCUGCGGCCGCCCCCCUCCCGACGUGGACGGCAUGAUCACCCUCAAGGUGGACAACCUGACCUACCGCACCUCUCCCGACAGCUUGAGGCGCGUGUUCGAGAAGUACGGGCGCGUGGGCGACGUGUACAUCCCGCGGGAGCCCCACACCAAGGCGCCCCGGGGCUUCGCUUUCGUCCGCUUUCACGACCGGCGCGACGCCCAAGACGCCGAGGCCGCCAUGGACGGGGCGGAGCUGGACGGACGCGAGCUGCGGGUGCAGGUGGCGCGCUAUGGCCGCCGGGACCUGCCCCGCAGCCGCCAGGGAGAGCCACGCGGCAGGUCCAGAGGCGGCGGCUACGGACGGCGGAGCCGCAGCUACGGGCGGCGGAGCCGCAGCCCCAGGCGGCGACACCGCAGCCGAUCCCGGGGUCCCAGCUGCUCCAGGUCCCGCAGCCGAUCUCGCUAUAGGGGUUCUCGCUAUAGCCGGUCUCCCUACAGCCGAUCUCCUUACAGCCGGUCGCGCUACAGCCGCUCUCCCUACAGCAGAUCUCGCUACAGGGAAUCUCGCUACGGCGGAUCUCACUACAGCUCAUCUGGUUACAGUAACUCUCGCUACAGCCGAUAUCACAGCAGCCGGUCUCACUCGAAGUCUGGGUCCUCCACUAGCUCUCGCUCUGCAUCAACCUCCAAAUCGAGCUCUGCGCGACGAUCCAAGUCCUCCUCGGUCUCCAGGUCUCGCUCGCGGUCCAGGUCUUCAUCUAUGACCAGGAGUCCUCCCCGGGUAUCCAAGAGGAAAUCCAAGUCAAGGUCGCGAUCCAAGAGGCCCCCCAAGUCUCCUGAAGAGGAAGGACAGAUGUCCUCUUAAGAAAAUGAUGCAUCAGGAAGCAACGUGAUGGAGGACUUGGGGGAAAAGGAUCACAUACUCAGUCUAUGGAAGCAACGUCCCUGGAAGAAGAGGCUGCCUAUUGAAAAGGUUGUGUCACACUUUUCUACCUUUUUGCCAGUUUGAAGCUUUGCAUCAGGUGGCAAAAUUCAUUCUAUGUGCCGUUUUGUUGUUAUUCACAUUUUAUUGUAACUUAGGAGGUGAACGACCUAAGAUUACGUUAUUGGGUUUGGAUAUUUGAGGCAAAAAUUUAUUUUUAUUUCUAUAGUGAUGACUGUUUUGGUUUGAAAUGAACAGAUUGGUAACCUAAUUUGUGGCCUCCUGACUUUUAAGGAAACGUGUGCAGCCAUUACACACAGCCUAACGCUGUCAAGACAUGCUUCAACAUUGCCUUCAUUCCUUAAAAACCUACAAAAGGUGGUGUAAAUUAAUAUGGAUAAUUUUAUUUACCUCCAGGUCUAAAAGGUAGUGUGACCCAAAUUUGUAUAAAGAUUUUUCAUGUGAAAGGACUGGGGUUUUAGCAAACACAGGUCUAAUCUCUUUUGUGUUUUUGUGCACCAGGCCCGGCUGCGUAGCAGUUGAGUGAUGCUGGUUAGCUAUUAAGGUGGCCUGUUGCAGUGCAGAGUGCUGAGCUGCUUCCUGUUUUCUUCUGAUUGCUCCUGGGGAAAACACGCCUUGUCCUGAAGAACAAAUGGCUGUCCAGUUUAUUAAAAUGCCUGUCAACUGCACUUCCAGUCACCCAGGCCUUGCAGAUAAAUAAUGGAGCAUGCAGUGAGCACAUCUAGCUGACGAUAAUCACACCUUUUCCCCCGUCUUUUCUGAAAAAUUGUAAAUCUGAUCAUAUCAACAUGUAUGAACUUAAAAUAUGGAGAAUGUUAUGGAAGAAAUAGUUUAUAAGUUUGUUAAGUACUUAUAACAUGGUUUAUCUUUUUGAUUAUUAAUUUUUUACGCUAACCAUUGUUUCUGUAGUUAAAAUUGUUUUCUUGGUGUUAUCUUUUCUCAGAAUAAAAUUAGAAACUUUUGAUGGAAAGUAGGUUGUUUUAUUUUCUGUAUGACUUUUGGAUAUUUGUACUUUUGAGAAAAUUAUUAGCACCAAGUGUUUCUCAAAAUAUAAUUUUUAAAAAAUCCUUAAUAGGCUUUUAGCUAUGUGCUUUAUUGUUUUAUCACAAUGCAGUUUAUUUGUAGUUUCUCUCUUUUUUCCUCACACCUAUGGUUUUUUUACUUCCAAAAUUAUUUUCAAAUAAUCCAUUUUUGGCUUUCAUCAUUAUCCCUACUAGAUGUUAUGUGUUCUUUUGCAAUUGUUUCUGCUUAUACCUUUACUAGCAAAGGGAAAAAUAACAAUUUGGUGUCAAUGAUCUGGUGACAAUAGGAUUACAUUGGAGCCAAUUGAAUAAAUUUAUUCUUUCAAUCAUAUGGAUCUUCAUUAAUAUUUUUGACUGAAUUAUCAAUUAAAAAUAUUUCAUUCCCUUUGUGCAGAAACUGCUAAAUCCAGGGUUCGAUUCUUGAAUGAACUGGCAAGGUGGCUGUGGUCUGUAGAUAUACAUCCCACAUUUUGUUGUUAUAACAGUUAGUAGUUAGUAUUGCUUUCAUAUAUAGACUCCAGAAUCUAAAUUUUACGAUAAUGACAUUUCUUCUGGUCAUGACAAAUGUAAUAUUUUACAAAUAUAAAUCUACGUAGAAUCCAAAGACACACACAGAGCAGUCCUGUCUGAGAAAUAAAAAAUCAGGACACCCAUGGCAUCGUAGUAGCCCCUCGCGUCCAGCAGGUGGCGAAGGGAGGUGAGGUAUAUUUAUUAAAUGGGACCGAGUGGGACGGGGACGGGGCAGCCCUAAGGGUAGGGAAGCAUUGUCAAUUUCUGGGGAUAGAAUGAGACCCAGGCAUAGCUGGAGUUUGAAGCUUUGAAGCAAAAAUAUCUGUAGAACAUCUUAAACGUGACCAAAAUAUGAUGUUAAAAUCAGCAACUCUUUAUACGUUAAAAACUUUGAAACCUGUGGCCGGGCAUGGUGGCUCGCGCCUGUAAUCCCAGCACUUUGGGAGGCCAAGGCAGGUGGAUCACCUGAGGUCAGGAGCUCAAGACCAGCCUGACCAACAUGGUGAAACCCCGUCUCUACUAAAAAUACAAAAAUUAGCUGGGCAUGGUGGCGCAUGCCUAUAAUCCCAGCUACUCGGAGGCUGAGGCAGGAUAAUCGCUUGAAACCGGGAGACAGAGGUUGUGGUGAGCCGAGAUCACGCCAUUGCACUCCAGCCGGGGCAACAAGAGCAAAACUUCAUCUCAAAAAAAAAAAAAAAAGAAAAAGGAAAAAAACAAACAAACAACAACUUUGAAACCUAGGAACAAUUUUGGACCUGUUGGAGCAGAAAUGUGUAGUUGUCAUUGAAGGUGUGAACAUACCCUACCUCUACUCUACAUGUGGAAGACCUGACCCACAGAGGACAUGAACCCAUGAAGAAGAGUGAUGUGACAUGUUUUGCAUUUUAUUAGUACCAUGAUCUAACCAACUGAGCUAACUGGCCACACCAUUUUAUCCUUUAUAAUGAUCACUAUGAGGGCUGAGUGCAGAAUGGAGUGUAUGUGGUCAAGAGUGGAAGCUGUGAGGCUAUUGCAGUAAUCCAGAAAGAAAGGUGACAAUGGCUUAGACUUCAGUGGUAGUGUUGGAAAUGGACAUAAAUAGACAUAUUCAGGAAAUAUAUUGAUCUUAGAUCUAAUAAGACACGUAAUAGAUUAGAAGUAGGGAAAUUAAUGAAAAAGCAGAAUUAAGGAUGACUUCUCACUGGCUUGAAAUGCUAAAUGGAUGACGGUGCUGUUUAGUGAGUUGGGGAAGACUGGGCGUGGUGAUGGGUGUAGAAAUUGAGAAAGGAAAAUCAAGAAUUUCCAGAACUUUCAGAGCAAUGUUAAAUACUUUCCUUGAUAGUGGGUCAGUCAUCAUUUAUAAGUGCAUUUCUAAAAAUAUUGCUUAAUUUUGUUUUUGAGCUUUGUAUAAGUGGAAUUUUGUGUGUACUGAUUAUUUUGCUCAAUACUAUGUCUUUAAGAUUCUCUGUAUUGUUGCAUGUGGCUGAGUUUAUUUUUGAUGCUGUGUAGUGUUUUACUAAUUAAUAAAUCAUAAUUCAGUUUUUACUGUUCUAUUGAUGGA